UCCAGUACGAACGGAUCUUCAGUGUGCGCAAUACCUGCAUCUACCUGGUCAUCACCUGGAUCAUGACCGUCCUGGCUGUCCUGCCCAACAUGUACAUUGGCACCAUCGAUGUGCUGGUGCCCUAUCAACGUGCUCACUGUCUUGGUGGCUGUCAGUCCGAAGGAGAUGGCAGGCAAGAUCCCCAACUGGCUUUAUCUUGCAGCCUACUUCAUAGCCUACUUCAACAGCUGCCUCAACGCUGUGAUCUACGGGCUCCUCAAUGAGAAUUUCCGAAGAGAAUACUGGACCAUCUUCCAUGCUAUGCGGCACCCUAUCAUAUUCUUCUCUGGCCUCAUCAGUGAUAUUCGUGAGAUGCAGGAGGCCCGUACCCUGGCCCGCGCCCGUGCCCAUGCUCGCGACCAAGCUCGUGAACAAGACCGUGCCCAUGCCUGUCCUGCUGUGGAGGAAACCCCGAUGAAUGUCCGGAAUGUUCCAUUACCUGGUGAUGCUGCAGCUGGCCACCCCGACCGUGCCUCUGGCCACCCUAAGCCCCAUUCCAGAUCCUCCUCUGCCUAUCGCAAAUCUGCCUCUACCCACCACAAGUCUGUCUUUAGCCACUCCAAGGCUGCCUCUGGUCACCUCAAGCCUGUCUCUGGCCACUCCAAGCCUGCCUCUGGUCACCCCAAGUCUGCCACUGUCUACCCUAAGCCUGCCUCUGUCCAUUUCAAGGCUGACUCUGUCCAUUUCAAGGGUGACUCUGUCCAUUUCAAGCCUGACUCUGUUCAUUUCAAGCCUGCUUCCAGCAACCCCAAGCCCAUCACUGGCCACCAUGUCUCUGCUGGCAGCCACUCCAAGUCUGCCUUCAGUGCUGCCACCAGCCACCCUAAACCCACCACUGGCCACAUCAAGCCAGCUACCAGCCAUGCUGAGCCCACCACUGCUGACUAUCCCAAGCCUGCCACUACCAGCCACCCUAAGCCCACUGCUGCUGACAACCCUGAGCUCUCUGCCUCCCAUUGCCCCGAGAUCCCUGCCAUUGCCCACCCUGUGUCUGACGACAGUGACCUCCCUGAGUCGGCCUCUAGCCCUGCCGCUGGGCCCACCAAGCCUGCUGCCAGCCAGCUGGAGUCUGACACCAUCGCUGACCUUCCUGACCCUACUGUAGUCACUACCAGUACCAAUGAUUACCAUGAUGUCGUGGUUAUUGAUGUUGAAGAUGAUCCUGAUGAAAUGGCUGUGUGAAAAAUGCUCUCGUAGGUGGCCAGGCAGUGGUCCCCUUUCUAGUUUGUUUUGCAUAUGUAAUCCAAAGUGAGAUGCCUUACUGCAUCUAGACACAGACACUGACACAUAGAGAUGGUGUAAGCUACAUCCACCUUUCAGGCGUACUCAUCCUUUACUUAAUGUACUGUAUUAAAGUGUGUGCGUGGGUGUGUGUGUGCUUGCUAUUUUAGAGACCUUAAUUUCCCUCAAGUUUGACAUCUGUUGUUCCAAACCUCCCUUUCCAACUAUGGUCGACCUUCAGUCCUCAGUGAUCCUUGAAAUUUUAGACUUUGAUUUUUUUCCCACUCCUCUGUCCCUCCUCCCCUUUCCUCAUUUCCUCUGCCUUGUUCCUGCUUUCUUCUCCCAUUCCCCGAGGGGGUUGGGAGAGGGGUAUGUGCGCAAUGCUAAAGGUGUGUUGUGGUGAACGCUUCCGUUAAUGUGACUGCACAGCUUUAUGUUCUUCAAUGUGUAACUCUAUAUUGUACUUUUAAUAGCAGUCAGAAAAGCAGUUGUGAUCAAGUACAAGUACUGGAAAGUUUCUUUCCUAAAUUUCAGCAACAACAUAUGACCCAUAUUUGAAGAAUACAAUUUGAUAAGCUCUUAUUAAAAAUACAUUUUUUAUGCCUAUGAGAUCAAAUGGCAAAAGGAAAGAUAUGGGCACACCAAAUUAUUUCUAUUUUUUGAAAAUUUGAACAUUGGUGCUUUUUAUAGUCAAACAUGGUUGCAAAUGAUAAGACGUUUUUACCUUAUUUGUAAUUAUUUACCUUUUUUAGCAUUUGCCGGGAUUUUUUUUCAUUUAGUUCCAGAGAAAUAAAUCCAUUCAUAAACUAGUUUCUUCUCCUAAAAUCCAAUCUUACGGUUGCUAGGAUCAAUUAUGGUAAUAUUUUUAAUAUUAUAAGUCAUAACUACUCUUUACUGAAGAUUUUGUUUUUUAAACAGCCUGGUGUUUUUACAGUUUUUGCAUUAUUGCUUUCAUUCAAAAGGGAAUUUGAAGUAAUAAAUGGCAGCAAGAAGCGAAUUGAAUACUGCUGGGAGGUUGUAAAUGAGCAUUCCUCCCGGAUGGGGAGGGGGGCAAGGAGAAGAAAGAGAUGCCUACACCAAUCAAUCCUACCACACAUCCGACAUCAGCCAAUCCCACCACACUUGGCUAAGGUUCAGUGAUACACGAUGUUAAGUCGUAGAUGUCUUUUAUUAGCACACUUGACAGACCAGGAAAUGAUUUUUCUCUACAAUUCAAGAAAACUGCUGUUUAAUAAAAAUUUCAAUUGCUGAUUCAAAUAGACACUUUAAGCAAAGUUUACUGUAUGAAAGCUUGUGAGGAUAAGUGGAAAUGUAUUAUACUGCCUUAAUUCUAUUCUGUAUUUGUGGUAGCAAUUAAAUAGAAGUGUUUUUGUGGCUUUA